AGAGCCCGUGCGGAGGCGGUGCGGAGCAUUUCGGCUCUGAGCGGCUGGGCGACCGGCGCGUCGUGCGGGGCUGCGGCGGAGCCUCCUUAAGGAAGGUGCAAGAGGUUGGCAGCUUCGAUUGAAGCACAUCGACCGGCGACAGCAGCCAGGAGUCAUGAGCGACAGCGGCGAGCAGAACUACGGCGAGCGGGAAUCCCGUUCUGCUUCCAGAAGUGGAAGUGCUCACGGAUCGGGGAAAUCUGCAAGGCAUACCCCUGCAAGGUCUCGCUCCAAGGAAGAUUCCAGGCGUUCCAGAUCAAAGUCCAGGUCCCGAUCUGAAUCUAGGUCUAGAUCCAGAAGAAGCUCCCGAAGGCAUUAUACCCGGUCACGGUCUCGCUCCCGCUCCCAUAGACGAUCACGUAGCAGGUCUUACAGUCGAGAUUAUCGUAGACGGCACAGCCACAGCCAUUCUCCCAUGUCUACUCGCAGGCGUCAUGUUGGGAAUCGGGCAAAUCCUGAUCCUAACUGUUGUCUUGGAGUAUUUGGGCUGAGCUUGUACACCACAGAAAGAGAUCUAAGAGAAGUGUUCUCUAAAUAUGGUCCCAUUGCCGAUGUGUCUAUUGUAUAUGACCAGCAGUCUAGGCGUUCAAGAGGAUUUGCCUUUGUAUAUUUUGAAAAUGUAGAUGAUGCCAAGGAAGCUAAAGAACGUGCCAAUGGAAUGGAGCUUGAUGGGCGUAGGAUCAGAGUUGAUUUCUCUAUAACAAAAAGACCACAUACGCCAACACCAGGAAUUUACAUGGGGAGACCUACCUAUGGCAGCUCUCGCCGUCGGGAUUACUAUGACAGAGGAUAUGAUCGGGGCUAUGAUGAUCGGGACUACUAUAGCAGAUCAUACAGAGGAGGAGGUGGAGGAGGAGGAGGAUGGAGAGCUGCCCAAGACAGGGAUCAGAUUUAUAGAAGGCGGUCACCUUCUCCUUACUAUAGUCGUGGAGGAUACAGAUCACGUUCCAGAUCUCGAUCAUACUCACCUCGUCGCUAUUAAAGCAUGAAGACUUUCUGAAACCUGCCCUAGAGCUGGGAUAUUGUUUGUGGGCAAUAUUUUUUAUUGUCUCUUGUUUAAAAAGUGAACAGUGCCUAGUGAAGUUAGGUGACUUUUACACCUUUUACGAUGACUACUUUUGGUGGAGUUGAAAUGCUGUUUUCAUUCUGCAUUUGUGUAGUUUGGUGCUUUGUUCCAAGUUAAGUGUUUUCAGAAAAGUAUGUUUUGCAUGUAUUUUUUUACAGUCUAAAUUUUGACUGCUGAGAAGUUUCUAUUGUACAAAACUUCAUUUAAAAGGUUUUUCUACUGAAUCCAGGGUAUUCUGAAGAUCGAAGCCUGUGUAAAAUGCUACCAAAUGGCAAAAAGCAACAAUAAACAGUUUGAUUUUUACUUUUCUUUCUAACAUAUCAAUGCUUAGCAGAACUAUUCAGAUUGUCAGUAGUAAAUUUAAAGACAAAUGCCCGUUUUCCUCCAGUCCAUGAAACAUACCAUACUUAUAUACCUGCAACUAAGUGUUUAAAAUUAUGCUCUGUAACUCUGUACUGCUAGUAUUAGAACUAAAAAUCUUAAAAUACAGCCAGUGCUUAAUGCUUAUAUCAAUGUGGAUUUGUCGGCUUUUAUGUAAUCUGUAAUAUGUAUAGCAGGAAAUACGAAGAGUUACACAGUGUAUGCCUUAAAAGGCUGUUUCUUAAAGGUGUUACAAGGGGAUAAUGGUAUUUCAACUAGUUAUCAGCAAGUGACAAUACAUUCCACCACAAAUACACUCUUGUUCUUCUAGCUUUUAGACUAUAUGAAAAAACCGGGUGCUUCAAAGUACAUGAUAAGGGAACACUAUACCUGUCAUGGAUGAACUGAAGACUUUGCCUGUUCAUUUUUUAAAUAUUAUUUUCAGGUCCUUUGCUUACCAAAGGAGGCCCAAUUUCACUCAAAUGUUUUGAGAACUGUGUUUAAAUAAACGCAAAUGAAAAGAAAAAUGUUGGUGCAGCUGUUCACAAAGAAGUGUUCUUGUUCUAUUAUAAUUAGAGUUCUUCUGUAGUUUAAUCGUUAGGGCAGUGUGUUCCUUGGGCUGAGGUGUAUCUUUGCUAUUUUGGGCUGGGUUGAGGGGGGGAUGAAUUUCUGUAUUCCUGGAAAAUUCAGAGUGCAUAACUAGGUAUUAGAGUGAUCUCCAUUUGGGGAUGGAGUUACAGUAAAUAACUAGACUGCGGGUACUUUAAUACAUGUUCUUAUUAUUUUGCAUUUAAGUAAUUUUCAUGACCAAUUGUAGGGAUGUUGCUACAGGUGGGUUAUUUUGUUGCCUUGCUAACCUUUAUCGCAUCUAGGUAUUAGUAUGUUUCAGGUACUUUGGGAAGAACUUUACAUAUAAUCUUUAGCAAUGAAAUGAUGUAGAGUAACUUACCUUAGUUCAAAUAGCUGUUUAAGUGGCAAUGCCACGAUCUGAAUUGAACCUAGGUGAUCUUAGUCCACAGUUCUCUUGAUCAUGAUGUCUCAAAUCUGGGUACCUGGGUGAUGGAAAAUACCAGUAAUGGAGCAUAGGCAGUAUUGGCAGGUCUUAAUUUGUAAAACUUACUGUCCAGGGUGUUUUCAGUGUUUGCCAACUUGUGGUAAAUUAAUAUGCUUAGAGAACUACCCUUAGGUUUGUUUCUGAUAAGCAUGUGGAAACAACUUAGUAUAUGCCUGAUGGGUUAUUUCAAAUUGUUCUCAAUGAGUUUUGAAACAAGAAUUUGUAGUAUUUAUAUAUAAAGUUGAGUUUUAGGGUGUGGUCCCAGAGGGGGUUGUGUUAUGGAUGGAUACAUUAAAGGCUGAGAAACCUGGUUUUAUCGUGGUAGUAUAUACAGGCAUCCUUUCCUGAAGUAACUACAUUCUCCACCAUUUUCUCCCCAACCAAACCUCUCCCCAUCAGUUAACUGAUGGCUUGCGAGUUCACACUCCUGAUAAUCUCGAACAUAACCCUCGGUUUCUAUCCUAAAGCCUGAGUUUUAGCCCUUUAGUUGUGUAGCCAUCCUUUAUCCUGCUGAUUGAAAGUUUCCUUUUUUAGGCUAGUUUGAGUUGUUUUCUGGCUUUUAGAUUUGAAAGAAUUUUAGCCAUUUGACAUGGCUACAAAGAGUGUUAACAGGCAAAAGACUGAGGAAAAUUUGGAAUUUUACCAAGUUGAGAUAGACUGAGAAGUAGUGAGACAAAGUGGUAGUCUUUUGAUGUGCUGUAAUGCUAGUCGCCAGUUUCAUGAAAGGGAGGCAGCAGUUACCCGUAGGUAACCCCUAGGUAACUGCUGCCAUGGGCAGCUGAAUCAGACAAAAGCCAUGGGAAAGGAUAAAUUUGAGUCUUAAAGUUACUGCCUCAAGGCAAAGGGACUUGGAGGCUUUUAUAUGCCAAUACAAACAAUCCAUUUCUUAUAGCUGUAGGGCUGAGACUACUAAAACCAAAUGUAAAGUUCAUUUGGAAGAUUGCUAAGUUAAAUAGUUUUAUACUAGGCUUUUGUGAAACUUCUCAGGAAAUCAACAGGGUCCCAGCAAGUGGAAAUAAGGCUGUGUCAAAAGAUUUGUAGACCUGGGAGCAGGGGUUUCCGAUCUCCUGGCCAUGGAUUGCCUGAGCUCCGCCGCCUGUCAGAUCAGCAACAGCAGAUUUUCAUAGCAGGAAUCCUAUUGUGAAGUGCGCUUGAGAGGGAUCUAGCUUGCACAUUUCCUUAUGGAAAUCUAACUACAUGUUAGAGAAUGCUCAAGGUCUGCAAUGUUUACAUUGUUGCCCCUACAUAAGGAAUAUAUGCCUUAAGAUAAAACUAAUAGCUCUUAGCCCUCUUACACCAUUGACUAGGAUUCCAAUUCUGCAAGGCCCAGGAGGAGAAAUUGAGAAUUAGAAGUUUCACCGAGAAGAAAUAAAAAGAUUUGGUUUGCAUUAUCAAAAUUUCUGUAAAUUAUAUGGAAAUUUUGAGGAUGGAUUAGGCUGGAUUUAUUAGCAGUGGACACGCCUCCAAUAUUCCUUCAGCAUGCCAUCUCAGUGGAUUUUGAUUGGCUCUUGUAGGAUUGGACUUAAUGCUAGCUUAUGCCAAAUGUCAUCAAAAAGCCAGAAUGCUACUACAGUAAUGUAAAGGAUUAUUGUAUAUAGUGUAAAGGAUUAUUAUGUGUAAUCUUUAAUAUAUAAUGUAAAGACUUAAAAGUGACAAGAA